AAGCACCGCGUAGGCCAGCUGGCCGGAUCCCGCCGUCUGUCAUGGCGGCCCCCAUCCUGAAAGAUGUAGUGGCCUAUGUUGAAGUGUGGUCAUCCAAUGGAACAGAAAAUUAUUCAAAGACAUUUACAACACAGCUUGUGGAUAUGGGGGCAAAGGUUUCAAAAACUUUUAACAAACAAGUAACUCACGUUAUCUUCAAAGAUGGCUACCAGAGCACUUGGGACAAAGCUCAGAAGAGAGGCGUAAAGCUCGUUUCGGUGCUCUGGGUGGAAAAAUGCAGGACAGCUGGAGCACACAUUGAUGAAUCAUUGUUCCCUGCAGCUAAUAUGAAUGAACACUUAUCAAGCCUAAUUAAAAAAAAACGUAAAUGUAUGCAGCCCAAAGAUUUUAAUUUUAAAACACCAGAAAAUGAUAAGAGAUUUCAGAAGAAAUUUGAGAAAAUGGCUAAAGAGCUACAAAGGCAAAAAACAAAUCUAGAUGAUGAUGUACCUAUUCUCUUAUUUGAAUCUAAUGGUUCAUUAAUAUAUACUCCCACAAUUGAAAUUAAUAGUAGGCACCACAGCGCAAUGGAGAAGAGAUUACAAGAGAUGAAGGAGAAAAGGGAAAAUCUUUCCCCCACCUCUUCCCAAAUGAUUCAGCAGUCUCAUGAUAAUCCAAGUAACUCUCUGUGUGAAGCACCUUUGAACAUUUCACGUGAUACUUUGUGUUCAGAUGAAUACUUUGCUGGUGGCUUACACUCAUCUUUUGAUGAUCUUUGUGGAAACUCAGGAUGUGGAAAUCAGGAAAGGAAGUUGGAAGGAUCCAUUAAUGACAUUAAAAGUGAUGUGUGUAUUUCUUCACUUGUAUUGAAAGCAAAUAAUAUUCAUUCAUCACCAUCUUUCACUCACCUCGAUAAAUCAAGUCCUCAGAAAUUUCUGAGUAAUCUUUCAAAGGAAGAAAUAAACUUGCAAAGAAAUAUUGCAGGUAAAGUAGUCACCCCUGACCAAAAGCAGGCUGCAGGUAUGUCUCAGGAGACGUUUGAAGAGAAGUAUCGUUUGUCUCCUACCUUAUCUUCAACAAAAGGCCACCUUUUGAUACAUUCAAGACCCAGGAGUUCCUCAGUAAAGAGAAAAAGAGUAUCACAUGGCUCCCAUUCACCUCCGAAGGAAAAAUGCAAGAGAAAGAGGAGCACCAGGAGAUCUAUCAUGCCGAGGCUGCAGCUGUGCAGGUCGGAAGACAGGCUGCAGCACGUGGCGGGACCUGCCCUGGAGGCUCUUAGCUGUGGGGAGUCUUCAUAUGAUGACUAUUUUUCACCUGAUAAUCUUAAGGAAAGGUAUUCAGAGAAUCUUCCUCCUGAAUCUCAGCUGCCAUCAAGCCCUGCUCAGUUGAGCUGCAGAAGUCUUUCUAAGAAGGAGAGAACAAGCAUAUUUGAAAUGUCUGAUUUUUCCUGCGUUGGCAAAAAAACCAGAACAGUUGACAUUACCAAUUUCACAGCAAAAACCAUCUCCAGUCCUCGGAAAACUGGAAAUGGUGAAGGCCGUGCAACUUCGAGUUGCGUGACUUCUGCCCCUGAAGAAGCCCUAAGGUGUUGUAGACAGGCUGGGAAAGAAGACGCAUGCCCAGAGGGAAAUGGCUUUUCUUACACCAUUGAGGACCCUGCUCUUCCAAAAGGACAUGAUGAUGAUUUAACUCCUUUGGAAGGAAGCCUUGAAGAAAUGAAAGAAGCGGUUGGUCUGAAAAGCACACAGAACAAAGGUACCACUUCCAAAAUAUCAAACUCCUCUGAAGGCGAAGCCCAGAGUGAACAUGAGCCAUGUUUUAUAGUUGACUGUAACAUGGAGACGUCUACAGAAGAGAAGGAAAACUUACCCGGAGGAUACAGUGGAAGUGUUAAAAAUAGACCAACAAGGCAUGAUGUUUUAGAUGACUCAUGUGACGGCUUUAAGGACCUCAUCAAACCUCAUGAGGAAUUGAAGAAAAGUGGGAGAGGCAAAAAGCCAACAAGAACAUUAGUCAUGACAAGCAUGCCAUCUGAAAAGCAGAAUGUCGUCAUCCAGGUUGUGGAUAAAUUGAAAGGCUUUUCAAUUGCACCAGACGUCUGUGAGACCACGACUCACGUGCUUUCCGGGAAGCCACUUCGCACCCUGAAUGUGCUGCUGGGAAUUGCGCGUGGCUGCUGGGUUCUCUCUUAUGAUUGGGUGCUAUGGUCUUUAGAAUUGGGUCACUGGAUUUCUGAGGAGCCGUUCGAACUGUCUCACCACUUCCCUGCAGCUCCCCUGUGCCGAAGCGAGUGCCACUUGUCUGCAGGGCCGUACCGCGGAACCCUCUUUGCCGACCAGCCAGCGAUGUUUGUCUCGCCUGCCAGCAGCCCCCCAGUGGCCAAGCUCUGUGAACUAGUCCACCUGUGCGGAGGCCGGGUCAGCCAAGUCCCCCGCCAGGCCAGCAUCGUCAUCGGGCCCUACAGCGGAAAGAAGAAAGCCACAGUCAAGUAUCUGUCUGAGAAAUGGGUCUUAGAUGGAGUCUCGCUGUGUCACCAGGCUGGAGUGUGCAGUGAUGAGAUCUCAGCUCACUGCAACCUUCACCUCCUGGGUUCAAGUGAUUCUUCUGCCUCAGCCUUCCCAGUAGCUGGAAUUACAGGCCCCGCCACCAUGCCCAGAUUCCAUCACCCAGCACAAGGUCUGUGCCCCUGAAAACUACCUAUUGUCACAAUGACAGUGACCUCACUGGCCUGUGGUGACUGCACACAGCUCGCAAAACUGUCUUUGGAUGUUCAAAUGAGAAACAAAACUGUGAAGAGAAGGAACUGGCGUAUACAAGAUGACUUCUGAUAUCAUGUUUGCCAUGUGUUGUGGUUCUUAAGAACUCAUAGGUGACUUUCUGAUGACUGAAUGUCUGUUUCAGAGACGCUUCGGGCCUUUUUAUUUUUAUUUUAUUUUUUAUUUUUUGAGACGGAGUCCUGCCCUGUUUCCCAGGCUGGAGUGCAAUGGCACAAUCUCGGCUCACUGCAACCUCCACCUCCCAGGUUCAAGCGAUUCUGCUGCCUCAGCCUCCUGAGUAGCUGGGAUUACAGAUGUGUGCCACCAUGCCUGGCUAAUUUUUGUAGUUUUAGUAGAGACAGGGUUUCGCCAUGUUGGCCAGGCUGGUCUCAAACGCCUGAGCUCAGGUGAUCUGUCAGGCCUCUUCUAUAGAAUUCCAGUCUUUGUGUCUUAGUCAUGAUCAUAAUUGAAAGGUCACAGAACCUUUGUCAUUAGAGCACAGUACUGCCAAAUAAAGAAUGGAAAUUCAAUGACAUUGUUUUAUUACUGAGAACAACUAGAGAACUCUGCAAGUUUCUUGGCUUAGACUCGAUCUUUAUUAAUACAUUAUCUAUUAGGUAGGAAAGACAUUUGUCAGCUAUUAAGGUGACUUUUAUCUAGCGGAGAUUCCUCUCUUAAAGUAAUGAAAGGAGAUAGGUAUGGGGGGUGUUAUACAGGAUAAUUGGUGACAUCUGAGUGUCUUACUUCUGCAAGCCUGCUUUAUGGUGAGCAAAGCAUCACCAGCAAGUGAUCACAAUGUCCACUGGCCGCUUUUUGCCUGCCGUCCUCGAGAUGAAAUUGGCAGUUGGGGCUGAUUCACAGAAACACCGAUUUGUGGCUGAGCACGGUGGCUCACACCUGUCAUCCCAGCCCUUUGGGAGGCUGAGGUGGACAGAUCACUUGAGGUCAGGAGUUCGAGACCAGCCUGACCAACGCAGCAAAACCCAUCUCUACUAAAAAUACAAAAAUCAGCUGGGUGUGGUGGCACACACCUGUGGUCCCAGCUCCUCAGGAGUCUGAGGCAGAAGAAUCGCUUGAACCCAAGAGGCAGAGGUUGCAGUGAGCCAAGGUUGCAGUGAAUCAAGAUUGCUCCACUGCACUCCAGCCUGGGCAACAGAGUAACUCUCCUUCUCAAAUAAAUAAAUAAAUAAAUAAGAAACACUGAUGUGUCUGUCACCUUCUAAAGAAAUGAAAUGCUAGGAAGUCCUAGCCAGAGUGAUCAGGCAAGAAUAAGCCAUAAAAGGCAUCCAAAUAGGAAAAGAAGUCAAACUGUCUCUCUUCACUGCCGAUAUGAUUCUAUACCUAGAAAACCCUAAAGACUCUGCCAAAAGGCUCCUGGAACCGAUAAAUGACUUAAGUAAAGUUUCAGGAUAGUAAAUCCAUGUACAAAAAUCAGCAUUUCCAAACACAGUAACAUUCAAGCUGAGCACCAAAUCAAGAACGCAAUCCCAUUUCCAAUAGCCACGGAAUGAAAUACCUAGGAACACGUAUAACCAAGGAGGCAAAGGAUCUCUACAAGGAGAACCAUAAACGAGAUGCUGAGUCCCAGCGAGGUCGGAGGUGCCACUGAGCCCUCAUCGUGGUGCCGUUCCCGCUCUGGGUUAUUUAUCUGUUGCUCAUCUCAGCUGUUGUUCCUACCUCAAAUUUCAAGUCCCUCAACAAAUAUAACAGAACCACUUCUAGAAUGAACCUUUGAGAAGGGAGGUAGCAGUGCAUUGUAUAGGAAUUGGCAUUCUAUAGAAAACCACAGAAACUGGAAAUAAUGAAGGGUUGUCUCUUGGUUUUAAAAUAAUGUAUACACCUAAAUCAUCCCCUUAUGAUACUCAUCCUCUAACAGCAAUUGAACUUCAAUACAAUGAGUCAUUCCUGAGUUCACUCGCUUCACAUUACAUAUGUUUCUCUAUAACCACAAGCAUCCUGGCUUGGUAGUGCUCCCACAGCACCAAAAAUCCCUGAGGAGGCUGACAAACAUUGUGCUGACUCAUGCUGGAGACAAGCCACAGAGAACUUCCAUCCCCCACCACAUCAGCCACGGAGCCAGCCCAGCCUCUGCCCACCCAGGCCUCAGUCCCCAGUGUUAAGUUCUGAUCCCUGAUGCUGGCCUGCCAGUGGCCAGUCAAGAUUCUCUUUCUGAAAGCUAGUAUUUUAUGAGGACUGACUGUUGCUAGACAUUACACUAAGCACAUUAUAUGUUGUACUUCAUUUUACCCUUUCAACAAUCCUAUUAGUAGCUUACUGUGGGUCUGCAAAGCCUUACUCAAAACAUAUAGGGCUAGAGGUUCUCAGGAUUCUGAAUUUUAAAAAAAAUUUGUAAAGGCUUAUGGCUCUCACCACUGUUAUUCAACGUUGCAUUAAAGUUUCUACCCAGAGAAGGCAAUAAAAGGAAAUUAAAGCUAUACAGAUUGGAAGUGAAGAAAUAAAAGUCUUUAUUCUCAAGAAUACAAGACACUAUGUAUAGAAAUUGUAAGGAAUGCAAAAAAAAAAAAAAAAAAAAGCCCUACAAGAACUUAUAACAAGUUUAGCAAGAUUGCAAUAUACAAUCUUGCAAUCUUCCUAAAGAUUAUAUACAAACCUAACAGAAUUGUAUUUAUAUAUACUGUCAAUAAGCAAUUCAAAAUGAAAUUAAGACCACGAUUCCAUUUAAAAUUGCAUCUAAAAAUAAACAAAAUAGGAAUAGACUUGGCAACAGUUGUAACAUCUGUAUACUGAAACCUGUAAAACAUUGCUGAAAGAAGUUAAAGACUUCUUUAAAUAGAGACAUAUACAAAGUUCAUAGAUUAGAAGAUGCAAUAUUGUUAAGAUGAUAGUCCUCAAAUUGACGUAUAGAUUCAAUGCAAUCCAUUAAAAUCUCAGAUGGCUUUUUAUAGAAUUUGAAAAGCUGAUGCUAAAUCUUUUAUGAAAAUGCAAAGAACCUCUAGUAGACAAAACAAUUUUUUUAAGAGCAAAGUUGGAGGAUUUAUAGAACCUGAUUCCAAAACUGUCAGUAAAACUACAAUAAUUACAAAGUAUCAGCCAGGUGCCGUGGCUCACAUCUGUAAUACCAGCUCUCUGGGAGGCUGAGGCGGGUGGAUCACUUGAAGUCGGGAGUUUAAGACCAGCCUGGCCAACUUGGUGAAACCUUGUCUCUACUAGAAAUACAAAAAAUUAGCCAGGCAUGAUGGCACACACCUGUAAUCUCAGUUACUCAGGAGGCUGAAGCAGAAUAGCUUGAACCCAAGAGAGUCCAGCUCAAAAACAACAACAAGAACAAAAGUAUCACAUUGGCAUAAGAAUAGACAUGUAAAUCAAAUAACAAAAUAGAGAAUUCAGGUAUAAAUCUUCAUAUUUAUGGCUGAUUGACUUUGAACAAAGGUGACGAGGCAAGUCAGUAUAGCAGCAUAUUCUUUUCAACAAAUGGUGCUGGCAGAAGAAAAAAAAAGUACUUGGAUCCUUACCUCACACCAUGCACAAAAAUUAGCUCAACGUGGACUAUAUCAGGGUUUCUCAACAUCAGCAGUGUUGGCGUUUGCUGGGGUGGAUAAUUCUUUCCUGUGGAGAGCUGUCCUGUGCACUGUAGAAUGUUUAGCUGCAUCCUGGCCUCUGCCUAUUAGAUGCCAGUGGCAUCCCUCCCCUGACACACACCUAGUUUUGACAAUCUCUGUCUCCAGAUAUUCCCAAAUGUGCCCUGGAGAGCAAAACUGUUUCCAGUUGAGAACCAUUGACCUAAUGUAAAAAAUAAAAUGUACAGAAGAAAGCAUAGCAGGAAAUCAUUCUGACCUCAGGUUAGGCAAAGCUUUCUUAGAUAUGACACUAAAGGCAUAAUUCAUUAAAAAAAUAAGUUGGGCUUUGUCAAAAUUUUAAGUUUUGCUCUUCUGAAGAAACCAUUAAAAAAAAAUGAAAAGACAAGCCACAGACUAUGAAAAAAUACUUGCAAAUCAUAUAUCUGAUAAAGGACUUGUACCCAGACCAUGUAAAGAACUCAUAACUCAUUAAUAAAAGGAUAAAGAAAAAGCUGAAGACAAUUCAUGCAAGAAGAUAUACAAAUAUUAAGCACAUUAAAAUGCUCAAUAUUAUUAGUCACUAGGGAAAUACAAAUUAAAGGCCCAAUGAAAUACCUAUUACACACCCAUUAGAAUGACUGUAAACAACAAGACUGAUAAUUCCAACAUCUGACCAAGAUAUGGAGAAACUAGAACUCUCCUACAUUGCUGGCAUGAGUGCAAAAUGAUACAGCCACUUUGAAACACCAUUUGGCAGUUGCUUAAAAAAUUGAACAUUCAACUACCAUAUGACCCAGCAAUUUCACUCUCAGGUAUAUAACCAAAAUACAUGAAAACAUGGAUCUGCACAAGGUCUUGUAUACAAAUGUUCAUAGCAACAUUAUUCAUAAUAACCAAAAAUUAGCCCAUCAACUGAAAAGUAGAUAAACAAAAUGUAUAUCCACACCAUGGAACGCUACUCAGCAAACUUCUAAAAAGCAACAAACUACUAAACACGUGCAACAACAUGAAUGAGCCUCAGAAACAUAAGUGAAAGAGGUCAGACACAAAAGACUACAAAUUGUAAGAUUCCAUUUAGAUACCAUUUCUACAAACCGCAAAACUGUAGAGGCACGAAACAGAUUCAUGGUCUGCUGCAGCUGGGGAUGGGAGUGGGAACAGAGAGCAAACAUUUUGGGAUGAUGGAAACAUUCUAAAACUGGAUUGUGAUUUUGGUUACACAACUGUAUACAUUUACUAAAAUCAAUGAACAGAACACUUUUAAUGGGUAAGCCUUAAGGCAUGUGAAUUAUACACCAAUAAAGCUAUUUUUUUUAAAAAAAAGAGAGAGAGAGAACGAGAGCUACAUGGCAGCCCCAGGGCAAUAGCUCUCAGAUCUCCCUUAGAGAAAGAACUUUCUCUUCCACAGCAAUGAGUGCAGGUAGCUAACACUGACCAACCUGCAUCUGGUAGUUCAUUUAAGGUCGGCCUUGGCUUUCAAGUUAAGGCCAUGGUCUUUCUCUGCAGUCCCCAGCCAAUACGUGGGCACAGAAAGGCACAGGGCAUGGCUGAUUCAGCCCAACAUGAGGCUCCACACCCUAGAACUCCCUGUGGAGUUGGCCGAUACUGCCUGUGACCUGCAAUGUGGUCUAAGCUGUCAGACCUCCACAGUGGCCAGAAGGUUUUCCAUACCUGAGCCUGCUUCUACCCACUUUUAUUUUUCCCAGGAGUCACGCUUAGUCAUCUCUUGCUCUUUGAACUCCAUGUCUGUAUCAGCUACCCAGAGGACCCAUCAGACAGAAAGUAAUAUGCAGAUAACAGCCCAGGGGAAUCUGGGCAGCACUGUGAAACCAACAUUUCUUCAGUGAAACCUAGAACAAAAGUGGAAUAAAUAAAAACUAACUGUCUCAUUUCAGCA